GUGAGUGGAGCUGGCAGCUCUGACGGGAGGGAGAAGGGAGGAGGCCCACGCGCAGGCAGUGUCUAUGUGUCCGUCCCCUGGGCACAGUUCCCCCAGCCUGUGGGAAGCCCCAGCAGCUGAACCGGGUUGUGGGCGGCGAGGACAGCACUGACAGCGAGUGGCCCUGGAUCGUGAGCAUCCAGAAGAAUGGGACCCACCACUGCGCAGGUUCUCUGCUCACCAGCCGCUGGGUGAUCACUGCUGCCCACUGUUUCAAGGAGUAUGUACAGCCGGCCUGGGGCACUUGAUCUUCUAAGGCCCUGGGCUUUGUGCCCCAGGCCCUGGGCUCCCUUUACAGGCUCUGCUUCCGGGCCUCUGUUCAAUCUUGGUGCCCCUCGAUUCUACCUAGAAGCCUCUCCUGCCUUCAGGGGCCUUCACACCCAUGCUGUUCCCCCAGGUACCUCCUCCCAGACCAGGCCUGGCUGAUCCUCCCCUUCCCUUUCCUUCCAGCAACCUGAACAAACCAUACCUGUUCUCUGUGCUGCUGGGGGCCUGGCAGCUGGGGAACCCUGGCUCUCGGUCCCAGAAGGUGGGUGUUGCCUGGGUGGAGCCCCACCCUGUGUAUUCCUGGAAGGAAGGUGCCUGUGCAGACAUUGCCCUGGUGCGUCUCGAGCGCUCCAUACAGUUCUCAGAGCGGGUCCUGCCCAUCUGCCUACCUGAUGCCUCUAUCCACCUCCCUCCAAACACCCACUGCUGGAUCUCAGGCUGGGGGAGCAUCCAAGAUGGAGUUCCCUUGCCCCACCCUCAGACCCUGCAGAAGCUGAAGGUUCCUAUCAUCGACUCGGAAGUCUGCAGCCAUCUGUACUGGCGGGGAGCAGGACAGGGACCCAUCACUGAGGACAUGCUGUGUGCCGGCUACUUGGAGGGGGAGCGGGAUGCUUGUCUGGGCGACUCCGGGGGCCCCCUCAUGUGCCAGGUGGACGGCGCCUGGCUGCUGGCCGGCAUCAUCAGCUGGGGCGAGGGCUGUGCCGAGCGCAACAGGCCCGGGGUCUACAUCAGCCUCUCUGCGCACCGCUCCUGGGUGGAGAAGAUCGUGCAAGGGGUGCAGCUCCGCGGGCGCGCUCAGGGGGGUGGGGCCCUCAGGGCACCGAGCCAGGGCUCUGGGGCCGCCGCGCGCUCCUAGGGCGCAGCGGGACGCGGGGCUCGGAUCUGAAAGGCGGCCAGAUCCACAUCUGGAUCUGGAUCUGCGGCGGCCUCGGGCGGUUUCCCCCGCCGUAAAUAGGCUCAUCUACCUCUACCUCUGGGGGCCCGGACGGCUGCUGCGGAAAGGAAACCCCCUCCCCGACCCGCCCGACGGCCUCAGGCCCCGCCUCCAAGGCAUCAGGCCCCGCCCAACGGCCUCAUGUCCCCGCCCCCACGACUUCCGGCCCCGCCCCGGGCCCCAGCGCUUUUGUGUAUAUAAAUGUUAAUGAUUUUUAUAGGUAUUUGUAACCCUGCCCACAUAUCUUAUUUAUUCCUCCAAUUUCAAUAAAUUAUUUAUUCUCCA